GGUAUCUCAGCAACCGCUGGGCAUCCGGAGGAUGUGGGGACGCGGAGCUGAGAGGCUCCGGGCUAGCUAGGUGUAGGGGUGGACGGGUCCCAGGACCCUGGUGAGGGUUCUCUACUUGGCCUUCGGUGGGGGUCAAGACGCAGGCACCUACGCCAAAGGGGAGCAAAGCCGGGCUCGGCCCGAGGCCCCCAGGACCUCCAUCUCCCAAUGUUGGAGUAGAGACAGGGUUUUGCCCUGUUGGCCAAGCUGGUCUUGAACUCCUGACCUCAAGUGAUCCACCCGCCUCGGCCUCCCAAAGUGUUGGGAUUACAGGCGUGAGCCAUCGUGCCCAGCCAGAUUCUCCAUUUCUAACAAGUUCCCAGGUGAUGUCGAUGAAGCUGGUUCGUGAACUGCACUUUAACAUGAUGUAGAAAUUUUACAAACUAGUAGAGUAAGGGGGUGGCUGCAGGCUGGAGAGGAAGUCCAGGCUAAACGCCUGGCAACUUGAGGUGGUUUCCGCCCCCUUGCUCGCUGAGGUUCCCUCCCAGGAAUCCGACACGUGACGGUCUGUCCGCCGUCUCAGACUAGAGGAGCGCUGUAAACGCCAUGGCUCCCAAGAAGCUGUCCUGCCUUCGUUCCCUGCUGCUGCCGCUCAGCCUGACGCUACUGCUGCCCCAGGCAGACACUCGGUCGUUCGUAGUGGAUAGGGGUCAUGACCGGUUUCUCCUAGACGGGGCCCCGUUCCGCUAUGUGUCUGGCAGCCUGCACUACUUUCGGGUACCGCGGGUGCUUUGGGCCGACCGGCUUUUGAAGAUGCGAUGGAGCGGCCUCAACGCCAUACAGUUUUAUGUGCCCUGGAACUACCACGAGCCACAGCCUGGGGUCUAUAACUUUAAUGGCAGCCGGGACCUCAUUGCCUUUCUGAAUGAGGCAGCUCUAGCGAACCUGUUGGUCAUACUGAGACCAGGACCUUACAUCUGUGCAGAGUGGGAGAUGGGGGGUCUCCCAUCCUGGUUGCUUCGAAAACCUGAAAUUCAUCUAAGAACCUCAGAUCCAGACUUCCUUGCCGCAGUGGACUCCUGGUUCAAGGUCUUGCUGCCCAAGAUAUAUCCAUGGCUUUAUCACAAUGGGGGCAACAUCAUUAGCAUUCAGGUGGAGAAUGAAUAUGGUAGCUACAGAGCCUGUGACUUCAGCUACAUGAGGCACUUGGCUGGGCUCUUCCGUGCACUGCUAGGAGAAAAGAUCUUGCUCUUCACCACAGAUGGGCCUGAAGGACUCAAGUGUGGCUCCCUCCGGGGACUCUAUACCACUGUAGAUUUUGGCCCAGCUGACAACAUGACCAAAAUCUUUACCCUGCUUCGGAAGUAUGAACCCCAUGGGCCAUUGGUAAACUCUGAGUACUACACAGGCUGGCUGGAUUACUGGGGCCAGAAUCACUCCACACGGUCUGUGUCAGCUGUAACCAAAGGACUAGAGAACAUGCUCAAGUUGGGAGCCAGUGUGAACAUGUACAUGUUCCAUGGAGGUACCAACUUUGGAUAUUGGAAUGGUGCCGAUAAGAAGGGACGCUUCCUUCCGAUUACUACCAGCUAUGACUAUGAUGCACCUAUAUCUGAAGCAGGGGACCCCACACCUAAGCUUUUUGCUCUUCGAGAUGUCAUCAGCAAGUUCCAGGAAGUUCCUUUGGGACCUUUACCUCCCCCGAGCCCCAAGAUGAUGCUUGGACCUGUGACUCUGCACCUGGUUGGGCAUUUACUGGCUUUCCUAGACUUGCUUUGCCCCCGUGGGCCCAUUCAUUCAAUCUUGCCAAUGACCUUUGAGGCUGUCAAGCAGGACCAUGGCUUCAUGUUGUACCGAACCUAUAUGACCCAUACCAUUUUUGAGCCAACACCAUUCUGGGUGCCAAAUAAUGGAGUCCAUGACCGUGCCUAUGUGAUGGUGGAUGGGGUGUUCCAGGGUGUUGUGGAGCGAAAUAUGAGAGACAAACUAUUUUUGACGGGGAAACUGGGGUCCAAACUGGAUAUCUUGGUGGAGAACAUGGGGAGGCUCAGCUUUGGGUCUAACAGCAGUGACUUCAAGGGCCUGUUGAAGCCACCAAUUCUGGGGCAAACAAUCCUUACCCAGUGGAUGAUGUUCCCUCUGAAAAUUGAUAACCUUGUGAAGUGGUGGUUUCCCCUCCAGUUGCCAAAAUGGCCAUAUCCUCAAGCUCCUUCUGGCCCCACAUUCUACUCCAAAACAUUUCCAAUUUUAGGCUCAGUUGGGGACACAUUUCUAUAUCUACCUGGAUGGACCAAGGGCCAAGUCUGGAUCAAUGGGUUUAACUUGGGCCGGUACUGGACAAAGCAGGGGCCACAACAGACCCUCUACGUGCCAAGAUUCCUGCUGUUUCCUAGGGGAGCCCUCAACAAAAUUACAUUGCUGGAACUAGAAGAUGUACCUCUCCAGCCCCAAGUCCAAUUUUUGGAUAAGCCUAUCCUCAAUAGCACUAGUACUUUGCACAGGACACAUAUCAAUUCCCUUUCAGCUGAUACACUGAGUGCCUCUGAACCAAUGGAGUUAAGUGGGCACUGAAAGGUAGGCCGGGCAUGGUGGCUCAUGCCUGUAAUCCCAGCACUUUGGGAGGCUGAGACGGGUGGAUUACCUGAGGUCAGGACUUCAAGACCAGCCUGGCCAACAUGGUGAAACCCCGUCUCCACUAAAAAUACAAAAAUUAGCCGGGCGUGAUGGUGGGCACCUCUAAUCCCAGCUACUUGGGAGGCUGAGGGCAGGAGAAUUGCUUGAAUCCAGGAGGCAGAGGUUGCAGUGAGUGGAGGUUGUACCACUGCACUCCAGCCUGGCUGACAGUGAGACACUCCAUCUCAAAAAAAAAAAAAAAAAAAAAAGUAACCCUUGGACCUGGGACAUGGAGUGGGCAGGAUCCCUUGGUGCUGGCCACGGUGACCCUAAGGAACUAAAGGCCACAGUGCCUCUGAAUGUAAGUACAAGUACACAUUCCUUGCCAAACUUUAUUGUGAUUAAAAUUCCAGAGACAGUACCAGCUCCACA